AGUGACAAUCAGGAAGUCGGCGUGUCGAGUGGCUCUUCCUGGCUGCUGAGGCGGGUUAAGGUCUGAGGGUCUUGUGGGGCCACGGCGCUGAUCACCAGGUGUUUGGCUUGGUCGGUUCUUAUUUCUCGCCUGGCAAUGGCGACGUACACCUGCAUAACUUGCCGGGUGGCGUUCCGCGACGCGGACAUGCAGCGGGCCCACUAUAAGACGGACUGGCACCGCUACAACCUGCGGCGGAAGGUGGCCAGCAUGGCCCCAGUGACCGCCGAGGGCUUCCAGGAGCGAGUGCGGGCGCAGCGGGCCGUCGCGGAGGAGGAGAGCAAGGGCUCGGCCACCUACUGCACCGUUUGCAGUAAGAAGUUUGCCUCUUUCAACGCCUACGAGAACCACCUCAAGUCCCGGCGUCACGUUGAGCUGGAGAAGAAGGCCGUGCAGGCAGUGAAUCGGAAAGUGGAGAUGAUGAAUGAAAAGAACUUGGAGAAAGGACUGGGCGUGGACAGUGUGGACAAGGAUGCCAUGAACGCGGCCAUCCAGCAGGCCAUCAAGGCCCAGCCGUCCAUGUCUCCCAAGAAGGCGCCCCCAGCGCCUGCAAAGGAGGCCAGGAAUGUCGUGGCCGUGGGUACUGGUGGCCGUGGGACCCACGACCGAGACCCGAGUGAGAAACCACCCCGGCUCCAGUGGUUUGAACAGCAGGCGAAGAAGUUGGCAAAGCAGCAGGAGGAGGACAGCGAGGAGGAGGAAGAGGACCUGGAUGGAGACGAUUGGGAAGAUAUUGAUUCUGAUGAAGAAUUGGAAUGUGAGGAUACUGAAGCAAUGGACGAUGUGGUGGAGCAGGAUGCAGAGGAGGAAGAGGCUGAGGAAGGCCCACCCCUUGGUGCCAUCCCUAUCACGGACUGCUUAUUUUGUUCCCAUCAUUCCAGCUCGCUGAUGAAGAAUGUGGCUCACAUGACCAAAGACCACAGUUUCUUUAUUCCUGAUAUAGAAUAUCUUUCAGAUAUUAAGGGACUGAUUAAAUACUUGGGAGAGAAAGUUGGUGUUGGCAAGAUUUGCUUGUGGUGCAACGAGAAAGGGAAGUCCUUCUACUCCACAGAAGCUGUACAGGCACAUAUGAAUGACAAAAGCCACUGUAAGCUCUUCACAGAUGGCGAUGCUGCUUUGGAAUUUGCAGACUUCUAUGAUUUUAGGAGUAGCUAUCCAGAUCACAAGGAAGGGGAGGACCCCAAUAAGGCUGAGGAGUUGCCCUCAGAAAAGAACUUGGAAUAUGAUGAUGAAACCAUGGAAUUGAUUCUGCCUUCUGGUGCCAGAGUGGGUCAUCGCUCCUUGAUGAGAUACUACAAACAGCGAUUUGGCUUGUCAAGAGCUGUGGCAGUUGCCAAAAAUCGGAAGGCCGUGGGCCGAGUACUUCAGCAGUACAGAGCCCUGGGAUGGACUGGCAGCACAGGAGCGGCUCUUAUGCGAGAGCGAGACAUGCAGUAUGUCCAAAGGAUGAAAUCAAAAUGGAUGCUGAAGACAGGAAUGAAGAACAAUGCCACCAAGCAGAUGCACUUUCGGGUCCAAGUGAGAUUCUGAGAGUCUGCUGGGAUUGAGCAAUCAUCUCCUGCCCAAGUUUCCUCCUUGCCCUGAGGACCAGUGAAAGACAGAUCAUAGGAGAGACCCUUUUGCUGCUACUUCAUUCGUUCUGACCUAAUAAUAAAAGUUAGAACCAUA